CCAGCUCUGACGCGGGAGCUUCUUUCACACCAAUGGGGCUCGCGCGCGGAGGGGCCCUGCCCCUCCUCCGGGAAGGUGUGUCCCUGUUUCCUCACCUGAAACUUCCUAGGAGAACCCGAUCCCUCCCUCCCGUCGGGCGGCCAGGGGCGGGCCGCGGGUGGGGCGGCCGGGCCUGCGCUGGGGACGGCUCUGGGGACUGCGGCCGGCGCCGGGACCUGGAGGGGACGCUGGGGCCGAAGCAGCAUGUGACACCGACCAGGAUUCAGCCCUGAUGGAGGCUGAGGAGGCCCAGCGUGGAGGCUGAGGAGGCCCAGCGUGGAGCCUCUCCUCCCAUCUCUGCCAUAGAGGAAUUCAGCAUUAUCCCUGAGGCUCCCAUGAGGAGCAGCCAGGUCUCUGCCUUGGGGCUUGAAGCUCAAGAAGAUGAGGACCCAUCCUAUAAGUGGAGAGAGGAACACAGACUCUCAGCAACUCAGCAGAGUGAGUUAAGGGAUGUGUGUGACUAUGCGAUUGAGACGAUGCCCUCUUUUCCCAAGGAAGGUUCUGCAGAUGUGGAGCCCAAUCAGGAAAGCCUUGUGGCUGAGGCCUGUGACACUCCGGAACACUGGGAGGCAGUACCCCAGAGCCUAGCAGGCCGACAAGCAAGGACUCUAGCUCCCCCAGAGCUCUGGGCCUGCCCCAUUCAGAGUGAGCAUCUAGACAUGGCCCCAUUUUCCAGUGACCUGGGAAGCGAAGAAGAGGAGGUGGAAUUUUGGCCAGGACUUACUUCUUUGACAUUGGGAUCUGGACAGGCAGAAGAAGAAGAGGAAACCUCUUCAGAUAACUCUGGUCAGACCAGAUAUUAUUCUCCCUGCGAAGAGCAUCCUGCAGAGACCAACCAGAAUGAAGGCUCUGAAAGUGGGACUAUCAGGCAGGGGGAAGAGCUGCCACCUGAGGAGCUGCAGGAAAGUCAAGGGCUCUUGCAUCCCCAGGAGGUCCAAGUUCUGGAGGAGCAGGGACAGCAGGAAGCAGGAUUUCGGGGGGAAGGAACUCUGAGGGAGGAUGUUUGUGCCGAUGGGCUAUUAGGGGAGGAACAGAUGAUAGAGCAGGUUAAUGAUGAAAAGGGAGAACAGAAGCAAAAACAGGAACAGGUACAAGAUGUGAUGCUUGGGAGACAAGGAGAAAGAAUGGGGCUCACUGGGGAGCCAGAGGGUCUGAAUGACGGUGAGUGGGAGCAGGAGGAUAUGGAGAGGAAGGCUCAGGGUCAGGGAGGUCCAGAACAGGGAGAAGAGAGGAAGAGGGAGCUGCAGGUGCCAGAAGAGAAUAGGGCGGACUCUCAGGACGAAAAGAGUCAAAUCUUUUUGGGAAAAUCAGAGGAAGUAACUGGAAAGCAAGAAGAUCAUGGUAUAAAGGAGAAAGGGGUGCCAGUCAGCGGGCAGGAGGCGAAAGAGCCAGAGAGUUGGGAUGGGGGCAGGCUGGGGGCAGUGGGAAGAGCGAGGAGCAGGGAAGAGGAGAAUGAGCAUCAUGGGCCUUCAAUGCCCGCUCUGAUAGCCCCUGAGGACUCUCCUCACUGUGACCUGUUUCCAGGUGCCUCAUAUCUCAUGACUCAGAUUCCCGGGACUCAGACAGAGUCCAGGGCUGAGGAACUGUCCCCCGCAGCUCUGUCUCCCUCGCUAGAGCCCAUCAGGUGCUCUCACCAGCCCAUUUCUCUACUGGGCUCCUUUUUGACUGAGGAGUCACCUGACAAGGAAAUAGAUCAAAACAGCCAGCAAGAGGGAUCCAGGCUGAGGAAGGGAACAGUGUCCAGCCAAGGGACUGAGGUGGUCUUUGCCAGUGCAUCUGUGACUCCUCCAAGGACACCAGAUUCAGCUCCUCCCAGUCCUGCUGAAGCCUACCCCAUCACACCUGCCUCGGUAUCUGCCAGGCCCCCAGUUGCCUUUCCCAGGAGGGAAACCUCUUGUGCUGCACGUGCUCCAGAAACUGCCAGUGCCCCUCUCUCAAUGGAUGACCCAUCUCCCUGUGGGACUUCUGAGAUGUGCCCGGCUGCCCUCUAUGGCUUCCCCUCCACCGGGACCAGCCCUCCGAGGCCCCCAGCCAACUCCACAGGCACCGUCCAGCACUUACGGAGUGACUCCUUCCCUGGUUCUCACAGGACAGAGCAGACUCCAGACCUGGUGGGAAUGUUGCUUUCCUACUCCCACUCAGAGCUGCCCCAGAGGCCCCCCAAACCUGCCAUCUACAGCUCUGUGACCCCAAGAAGGGACAGAAGGAGUGGUAGGGACUACAGCACCGUUUCAGCAUCCCCUACUGCCUUAUCCACGCUGAAGCAGGACUCUCAAGAAUCCAUCUCAAAUCUAGAGAGACCCAGCAGUCCUCCCAGCAUCCAGCCCUGGGUCUCCCCACAUAAUCCAGCCUUUGCCACAGAGUCUCCCGCCUACGGUUCUUCCCCAUCCUUUGUCUCCAUGGAGGAUGUGAGGAUCCACGAACCUCUGCCCCCUCCUCCCCCACAGAGGAGGGACACCCAUCCCUCCGUGGUGGAGACAGAUGGCCAUGCUCGUGUAGUGGUUCCCACGCUGAAGCAGCAUAGCCACCCUCCUCCAUUGGCCCUAGGUUCAGGGCUGCAUGCCCCCCAUAAAGGCCCACUUCCCCAAGCCUCUGACCCCGCUGUGGCCAGGCAGCACCGACCUCUGCCAUCUACCCCAGACAGCUCCCACCAUGCUCAGGCCACCCCCAGGUGGAGAUACAACAAGCCGCUACCCCCUACCCCUGAUUUGCCGCAGCCCCACCUUCCUCCCAUUUCUGCUCCUGGUAGCUCAAGGAUCUACAGGCCUCUACCCCCACUACCCAUCAUAGACCCUCCCACCGAACCACCCCCAUUGCCCCCAAAGUCCAGGGGGAGGAGCAGGAGCACUCGGGGAGGACAUAUGAACUCAGGGGGUCAUGCCAAAACAAGACCUGCUUGUCAAGACUGGACAGUCCCCCUCCCUGCCUCUGCUGGACGCACCUCCUGGCCCCCGGCCACAGCUAGAUCAACAGAGUCUUUCACUUCCACCAGCAGGAGUAAGAGCGAAGUGUCCCCUGGCAUGGCUUUCAGCAACAUGACAAACUUCCUAUGCCCCUCUUCCCCUACCACUCCCUGGACUCCGGAGCUCCAGGGACCCACCUCUAAGGAUGAAGCAGGGGUCUCAGAACACCCUGAGGCCCCUGCGAGAGAACCUUUGAGAAGGACAACCCCUCAGCAAGGAGCCAGUGGCCCAGGGAGGUCACCUGUGGGCCAAGCAAGGCAGCCAGAAAAACCCAGCCAUCUGCACCUGGAGAAGGCGUCCAGCUGGCCCCACAGGCGGGACUCAGGGAGGCCACCAGGGGACAGCAGUGGACAGGCUGUGGCUCCUAGUGAGGGGGCCAACAAGCACAAGGGCUGGAGCCGGCAGGGCCUGCGCAGACCUUCCAUCUUGCCUGAGGGCUCUUCAGAUUCAAGAGGUCCAGCCGUGGAGAAACAUCCGGGACCCUCAGACACUGUUGUUUUUCGGGAGAAAAAACCAAAGGAGGUGAUGGGAGGCUUUUCAAGACGCUGCUCCAAACUCAUCAACUCCUCCCAGCUGCUUUACCAGGAGUAUAGUGAUGUUGUCCUGAAUAAGGAGAUCCAGAGCCAGCAGCGGCUGGAGAGCCUGUCCGAGACACCCGGGCCUAGCUCUCCGCGGCAGCCUCGGAAGGCCCUGGUCUCCUCCGAGUCGUACCUGCAGCGGCUCUCCAUGGCCUCCAGCGGCUCCCUCUGGCAGGAAAUCCCCGUGGUGCGCAACAGCACCGUGCUGCUCUCCAUGACCCAUGAAGACCAAAAGCUGCAAGAGGUCAAAUUUGAGCUGAUUGUGUCAGAGGCCUCCUACCUGCGCAGUCUAAACAUAGCUGUGGAUCAUUUCCAACUUUCAACUUCACUCCGGGCCACACUUUCCAACCAGGAGCACCAAUGGCUCUUCUCUCGUUUACAGGAUGUGCGAGACGUCAGCGCCACGUUCCUUUCAGACCUGGAAGAGAACUUUGAGAACAAUAUCUUCUCCUUCCAAGUAUGUGACGUAGUCCUGAACCACGCCCCAGACUUCCGCCGGGUCUACCUGCCUUAUGUCACCAACCAGACCUAUCAGGAACGCACCUUCCAGAGCCUGAUGAAUAGCAACAGCAAUUUCCGGGAGGUCUUGGAGAAGCUGGAGAGCGACCCCGUCUGCCAGCGCCUUUCCCUCAAGUCCUUUCUGAUUCUGCCCUUCCAACGCAUCACCCGCCUCAAACUGCUGCUCCAGAACAUUCUGAAGAGAACACAGCCUGGCUCCUCGGAGGAGGCAGAGGCCACGAAGGCACACCACGCCCUGGAGCAGCUGAUCCGGGACUGCAAUAACAAUGUCCAGAGUAUGCGACGGACAGAGGAACUAAUCUACCUGAGCCAGAAGAUUGAGUUUGAGUGCAAAAUAUUCCCGCUCAUUUCUCAGUCACGCUGGCUGGUGAAAAGUGGGGAGCUGACAGCCUUGGAGUUCAGUGCUUCCCCAGGGCUACGAAGGAAGCUGAACACGCGUCCAGUCCACCUGCACCUCUUCAAUGACUGUCUGCUGCUGUCUCGGCCCCGAGAGGGUAGCCGAUUCCUGGUAUUUGACCAUGCUCCCUUCUCCUCCAUUCGGGGGGAAAAGUGUGAAAUGAAGCUACAUGGACCUCACAAAAACCUGUUCCGACUCUUUCUGCGGCAGAACACUCAGGGCGCCCAGGCCGAGUUCCUCUUCCGCACGGAGACUCAAAGUGAAAAGCUUCGGUGGAUCUCAGCCUUGGCCAUGCCAAGAGAGGAGUUGGACCUUCUGGAGUGUUACAGUCACCUGGAACAUCAAAAGAAAAAGAAAAGCUGUAAUAUUGAUGGGUGGCCUACUGUGCAACAAGAUUUUCAUAUAGUGUUUUUGGUGUUAUAUGGAUGUUUCUUCUCGCAGUGGAUGUGUAGAGUCAGAGCACAGAUGGGCAUACUCUCAAACCUUAACAACUGUGCCACAUUGCCCUUUGAGUUUAUUCUAAACCUUAGCAAGUCAGAGAUCACACUGUAUGGAACUAACUUCUAUCUAAAUUGCAUGAUUGAUUGAUAGGAGAUUUCCAAAUAACAUUUGGACUGCCUUACAUCCAGUAAAAGAACUCAGCAAAAUACAAAUAAAUAUGAUAAUAUCUUAGACAGCAAAUCUUCUCAUCCCACAAGAGGCAGGAAACUGCUAGAGGAAGCUGCCUUGGAGAGGAUUCUUUCCUCCCCUCCCGAAAGGAGCUGAACUCAAAAUCUCUCCAUUUCGCAAUAGACAUUGGAGAACAUUUUCAACAGUGGAUUUGCACCGGUGUUUUGUGUCCUAGAAAAACGUUCCCUUCAGGUAGGUUCUAAUAAGCCCCACUGGGACAUUUUGGACACCCUUGUCUGCUCUCUGCCUCUCUAACCUUAGAGGGUCCCUUGGAAUCAACUAAUAUUUCAGGUCCUUUCUUCCCAUUACUGUUGCCACACAAGGAACCCAGAUUACAUCAGGGAGAGGCUGAGCUCCAGAGGUUCACACCAGGAGCUUAGUCAUUGUCACACUGUUCCUGCUUCCUGACAGGUUCACUUGAACCAUCUGGAGAUUGGGGAACAAGGGCAAUGUGAGUAUUCAUGAAAUUCAAAUCAUGCCAAGUAUUCCGGGAUGGGAAUGGUUGUCUCAGAGGUGUGCUCUGUGGUUGACUGACCUUGAGCUUGCGUUUUCUUCCUUUUCUUUUUUUUUUAAAUUAUACUUUAGGUUUUAUGGUACAUGUGCACAUUGUGCAGGUUAGUUACAUAUGUAUACAUGUGCCAUGCUGGUGCGCUGCACCCACUAACUCGUCAUCUAGCAUUAGGUAUAUCUCCCAACGCUAUCCCUCCCCCCUCCCCCCACCCCAGAACAGUCCCCAGAGUGUGAUAUUCCCCUUCCUGUGCCCGUGUGAUCUCAUUGUUCAAUUCCCACCUAUGAGUGAGAAUAUGCGGUUUCUUAAUAUGUGUUUCUUAAUUGUGCAUCCUGCUGGGGUUGAGAACAGAAAUUGAAAAACACAAUUGUUUUAUCUCUCCUUCCCCGAGGAGUUGAACAUGUAGGAAGUUUCAUGGCCCAGCCCCUCCUGAGAGCCCUGAACUGCCAACCAGACUGAGCCCAUCAGAGAAUAACACCUCAUUUUCUGAGGAUUCUGAUACCUUUUCAAUCAGAAACAGAAGCAAAGAUUCUGCAGCUCCCACAGAAACUCCCAGAAACCUUGCGGUGCUUCACCCUUCUGAGAUCCUUGAGUCCGAAUGUGGGAGCUAACCAGGUUGCCUUUCUUUACUUACCAUGAAUUCCUCCUAGACUCGUGGUGGCACCUAGGCUUUGGUUCACUCUCACUCUGUUACUAACACUUUUUAUUAAGUAAUGGGAAGGGAAGUAAAUCAUUUAUUUUAUGGCUAAACAUAUAUGCUCAUUAUUCAUAUUAUAUAUCAAUGGUUCCAGGGGAAAAAUAGAUGCACAUUUGAUGUGCAAAUUAUGUAAAAGUGUUUAGGACUUGGCUAUAUAUGUUUCUUUGGUGGAGAAAUAUCUAUGUGAUAGAGAUUUCUUUGGGAAAGAUGACACUCACAAAAAAAGCCAGAAAUUUCUGUUUUAUAGAUUUUGAUAAAAUGUAUGAAAUAAUUUUCACAGCCAAAGGAAAGUAUAGCACAGUAUAUUAUGGAGAGAUGUUACAGCUCAGGAAAAUUAAUACAUGUCAGCUGUUUAAUAAAUUAUGCAUUUAAUUAUUGCCAGUACAGUCACAAUACAUGCUAAUCUAUGAGAAUAUAUUUAUUGCAAUAGAAUAUAAACCCAAAUGGAUGCUAAAUCUAUGUCUUAUCUUUCAUUAAGCAUGGCACUAAAGAGGGCAUAAGGCACCUGCAAUGUACUAGAUAAAUAUGUAUAAAUAUUAGAUUUUCCAUAGACUGGAGGAUAAGUUUUUGUGGUGCACAUGGAAAGAGUACAGAAAAAGAACUCAGGUGGUAGGUGGUGGUGUAACAAAGUAGGAAAACGAUGUAAUAAUUAAUAAUACUUUAAAUUUUCUUUUUAUAGGAUUUUUGUUUAAUGUGUACCUUUUUAUUUAUUUCUGCUUUUCCUCCCGAGGCACAUCUUCACAAUGAAAUCUUCACAAGCUCAGAACCAUCAACUUGCUACACUGUGUUCCUCCAGUGCCCAGUUCACAGGAAGCACUCAAGAGUAGGAUCAAUUGUUAUCAACCUCUAGCAGAUUAUUGAAUAGACGGUCGUUACAUGAAACUGACACUCAGUUCUUCAUGGUCCACGAUAGUUCUUAUAUCCAGAAAACGUACUUACGUUAUCAACUCUGACUCCAUAAGACAACUUUGCAAAGUCUUGGCUCAUAACUAUGUAAGCAAUGAGAUAACUUAGUUUUCAUUUCUCACUUGUUACUUACAAGUAAACAGCCCUGUAGCUCAGCUGAGCUACAGAUUAACUACAGGUAAUCACUUCAGCGAUUCUGCUUUACCCAUGCCCAAGAUUUUAAAAAAGAACCUGACAGAUCAUUAAAUUUUGAGAUUUGCUUUUUAAAAUGCAGGUUCCAUAAAGUUACGCUGUUUUGCUUAUAUAUACAGCAACAAAUGCCUUCUUAGAUAUUUACUUUAAAAUUCUAGUUUCCUUACCAUGUAUUAGCCAGAUAAUCUGUCAUUUUUUAAAUUCUGAAAUUGUACAUAUAUAAAUUAAUGUACAUCUCUAUGCCUGAAAGGUACAUUUGGAAUUACAACGUGUGUCAAGGUAGAGCAAAAUCCCCCAGUCCACUCCUUCCAACCCCCUAGAAAUUUACUCUGUUUGGUUUCCUCUUGAUUGUCUUUAAUUAACAAUAAGUAUGUCACAUAGGUAUCAAAUAAAAUAAGAAAAAAAAUAGAUAAAAGAGAAGUGAUUCAAAAUUCAAGUGUUUAAACACUUUAUGAAUCUUCCCGUUGUUCUUGACACAUUUUUAAAAUUUCAUUUUAAUUCAGAUCAUUAGGGAUGAAAUUCUCCUGAAUUGUAGCAUUUUAUUUCCUUUGGGAAGAAGGGGCUGAAUUUGGCAUAAUUAUACUUGACUAUACUGUAAAAGAAACCAGAUCUAAUAUAAGGACAUCAAUACUUAGUUAUUAAUUCAUUUGCUUAUAUUUAUAUGUCAUUUGAAAAUGUGUAUUAACAUACACAAUUAAAGGGAUAUAAAAAUGAACAUGCCCUCUCCAUUUCUUUAAAAGAAAUCAAGGCUGAAUCAAACAGGACUACUGUUCUGAAAGAAUACUCAGACUAUGAGGUACCUUAUUUUCCUUCUUUUACACCUGUCUUUCAGUUGGCUUCAAAAAAUCAUGGCUUUUACUGUGUUUCUUUUUUCCUUUAUGUCUUCCUUUUGAGGGAAAUGAAAAAUUGAGAAAGGAAAUUAUUAUUUUAUAAGUGGGUGGGUUUGAAUACAUCUUUCACAGUCAAAUAUUUUUCUAUGCCUUAUGAGCUUAAAAAAUAAAUUUAGAAAGUUUGAUAAACACAGAAAUUUUUUAUUUUAUGUUAUUUUAUGAGAUGAGGGCUUGCCAUGUUAUCCAGGCUGUCCUGGAACUCCUGGGCUCAAGCUAUCCUCCUGCUUUCAGCCUCCCAAGUAGCUGGAACUACAGGUGCAUAUGACGGCACCUACUGAGAAAUUUUUACUAUCAACCUAAAAUUUAAUAAGUCCUGGUCACAAGUGAGGAAUUUUUAAUUUGUUAUUUAGAUUAUUUUUGUGUCAAGGUAACUUGAUCACCUAUCAAUAAUGCUUAUAAGAAAAUAGAUAUCUCAUCUGUUGCUGUUAGAAAGGAAUCUGUCUCUUUCCCCAGUUCUUGCUUCAAUGAGGUUUCCUUGACCCAGAGUCUGGUCCUCACAUUUUAGAUUCAGCUUUGGGAAUUUUGUUCAGGAACUGCAUCAUACAACCCAAAAGCAAAAGAGGAAAAUGCAUAAGCCAGGAUACCUAAAUGUUCCUUUAUUUAAACUUGAAAAUGUGACUGCAAAAGGAGUCAAGAAGUUUAGUACUCAACACAUUUCUUCUUUGUAGAAAUAACUGCUCAAGAAGAUAAAUUGUUACCUAACAGUUGAUUGAUGAAUAUGAAAUCAGAGCAAGAGGGGCUAAUUAGAGAAAUUACUAGCUAGGGCUAUUUACCCAAACCAUCUAUCCAGACUGUAGACAUAGAAUCACCAGAUGGCUAGGAUCCUGGUGCAGCUGGUUCCCCUUUUUCCUUACCCUGAAUGUCAUUAAGGAUGCAUUGCCAAAUGCUGCCCCUCUGGCCUGAUGACUACACUCCAUAUUGGUCACCUGCCUUCUUUUUCCUACAGUCUUCCUCCAGACAGGCACGCCAUACAACCGACUACACUUGGGCUCACUGAAUGAAUCACAUUCUUCUGCUGUGCCUCCCAGAGAUUUCAUCAAAGCACCCGCAGUGGCCUUCUGGAGGCUCCUCAAACUCUCCACUCAAUGUUUCCUGAAAGUGUCGUGUUUCUCACCUCUAGAUUGUUAUUCUCAUCAGUUACAUGUGGGUUUCACAAAUUUAUUUCUCAGAAUGCAAGUCUGUCUCUUAUAUCCUCGGGAAACACACCUUUAUAUCCCAGUUAGUACUGACAAAAAUUAAACUAGGGACUGGCCAAAAACAGUGCCUUUCCUCACUUUAAUCUCACUAAAGUAGAUAAGACUCAAGUUAUUUUGUUCUUGCAAUGGCAUUGACAAAUGUUUGCACCAAAAACCAUGUUGAAGUUCAUUAAGGAAACUGUGAUCCAAGAUCCAAGGUCAAAAAAACAAAUUCAUCAAUUCAGCACACCACCAACUCACAGGCUAAGCAUCUUACUGCUAAUUCAUUGAUGCUGCCAUUUGUCAAGUGCCAAAUUGAAUUAUUGAUUUGUCAAUAAUUUCCUUCCGUUGGUUACUUAUAUAGUAUAUUGCAAUUCUUGUUGCUGAAGUCAGCUACACUUUUUCUAUUUGAAAAACAAUUUCUUGCAUUUGGGAUUUCAGGUAUAGUGAUUGUUACAAAUAUGAAGGACUUGAAUUAACAGCAAGUUUUCAAGUAAAACUUUACUUAUGUAUAACUGAAUGAGUUCUUAAAGACAUUUACUAACAAUUUUCCACAAACUAAAAAUUUAUAAAACAAUAAAUAAAAUAGACUUUAAAAAAAA